GCCCUGAAACCUUCUGGGAGGAGAAGAGGCCUGACCUUGGCGCUGGGGUCCAGUGGGCAUUGCUCUGGUCCGAGGCUGCUGCUCUUGACCUCUGCUCUGCGGCUGUUUUCCAUUGGAGUAGAGGCUCCUCCUGUCCUGUCCUGCCUGUGGAGGGAAGCAAACCUUCCCCUGGACCAGAGAGAGGAGAAAGCGGAGACAGGUAGCAACGCUGUGGACUGGUGAUGACAGGCUCUUCAGCUCCCUGCAAGUGACCGGGCCUGGGGAACAGGGCAUGGCACAGGCACACAGGACCCCCCAGCCCAGGGCUGCCCCCAGCCAGCCCCGUGUGUUCAAGCUGGUUCUCCUGGGAAGUGGCUCCGUGGGUAAGUCCAGCUUGGCUCUUCGGUACGUGAAGAACGACUUCAAGAGUAUCCUGCCUACGGUGGGCUGUGCGUUCUUCACAAAGGUGGUGGAUGUGGGUGCCACCUCUCUGAAGCUUGAGAUCUGGGACACAGCUGGCCAGGAGAAGUACCACAGCGUCUGCCACCUCUACUUCAGGGGUGCCAACGCUGCGCUUCUGGUGUACGACAUCACCAGGAAGGAUUCCUUCCUCAAGGCUCAGCAGUGGCUGAAGGACCUGGAGGAGGAGCUGCACCCAGGAGAAGUCCUGGUGAUGCUGGUGGGCAACAAGACGGACCUCAGCCAGGAGCGGGAGGUGACCUUCCAGGUACCGCCCAGGAGACCCUGCUCUGCUCUUCCACAGCAGGAGAGAGCCCUGCCCGCCUGUGUCAAGACCUUGGCACUCACACUUUCAUACACGCACACCCACACACGCACACACUUACACAUGUGCACACACACCUCUACACGCCCACAUGCAUUUACACACAUGCACACCCCCCACAUUCACUCUCACUUGCACCCACACACAUUUACAAGUGAACACACACACACGCACACACACACAGCUUUCCACCUGAGUUUCUCUUUUAGUCAAAGAUUUCCGGUCUUUCCUGAAAAACUCAGGCCCAGUGCAAUGGCAGUUCAAGCCCAGUGGCCGGCAGAGGGAAGGGCAGGGCGGCAGCUGCAGGGUGGGCUCGGCUUGAACGAGAAAAGUGAUCUAGUUCCUCAGCAGGGCUCCCUUCCCUACUCUGUUCCCAGAAGGGGCUUCUGUGCAAAUGUAGCCUCCUUCACUCGAGUUUUGUCAGUCCUCCUUACAGGCAGAGGCAGCGGUCACCCAGGUGUCGCUGUUGUUUCUCUUCCACGGCAUCCCACCUCCCCCACCACAUUUAGGACGAAGACCGUGUAAACAGCUGCAGACAAGUGGCUGAUGGGGAGACCCCACACACACUAGAGGCUGGCGCAGGGGAAGACCCAACUCAGGGCUUAGACCGACGGGCGCGCCUCCCAAAGAGAAAAGGCCCCAGCUUCAAUGGAGGCUGUGGAGAGAUGGAGAAGUGGGGUGAAGAUUUUGGAGAAUCUCGGGGGAGAGCAAGGGGAGCAAAGGGAGACAGCGUCAGUCUGAGCCCUCGUUGCAAGUUGGGGUGGGGGAGAGAGGAUCCUGGCAGCAGAGCUGUGCCCUCUGAGAGUGACUACAUGGGCUGUGUGCUUGGGCAGGCACAAAAACAUGGGCACGAGGUUACUCAAGGCUUGGAGGGGCAGUGGGCGGCCAGGGUGGGUUUGGAGCGUCUGUCUGGGGAGCUGGCUGGGGAGCUCAGUGGGGACAAAUGCAGGGCCGGCCGAGGGAUCUCCGGGCCAGGACAGGAGGAGUGCACUCACGAUGGUGGAUGGUGCGAGAGCUGGGGGCAUGGCCGGCCACACCUGCUGCCAGCUCCAUGUCUGGCUGGACAGUCAGGAGCCUGAGCUGUGCCCUCUGGGAUCCACCACAGGCUCCUCUUCCUGGGAGAGUCCCGGAGGCCAGGGGAGGGGCCUGCACAGGAAGGCCCCCAUUCCUCGGCCACCCUCGACUCCUGGGCAAGGCUGUGGCCUUCCCAUGAAUGCUUUCUCCUGGUCACCCGUUGCAAGCCUGCUGUUUUCUGGUUUGCCUUUGCUCUGGGACAUCCAUUUCUCCCCAGAGGAGAGCUGUGUUGGAAAAUGAGGGUUCCCCAGAAGAAGGGCCCAGGUGGGUGCCGUCCAGGGGCCUCCCUCUGCCUCAUGUUUCCUGGGUUCUCAGUUGGUUCUUUGCCCAGCAUCAAAGCCCACAGGUGCCAACAGGCAUGAUGGGAGGGGAACCUGGGGGUGGGGACUUGGCUUUCCAGGCCCUGCAGGAGGAGGAAGGCCGCACCCCGCCAGCUAGAGGAAGAGCCUCUUCCAGGGAGCACACCCCGCCCCUCCCUGGUCCUGGCUGCUCAGGAGUGCCAAGAAACACAACUUGGACACGAAACGUGGAGGAGUGCGGGCUCCACGGCUGCAGCUUUCUCGGAUCUUACUGUUGGAAGUGAACCAGGUGUCCUUAGGAAACUCUCUUAU